GAGCGCCGUUAACUUUUCCCCGAAGAGCAUGGCAGAGUGAAGCACAAGCAAUAAUCCUGUAUUAUUCGCGUUCCCAGAGUCCCUUCGGAUUUGCGCCAUGCGCGGCGGGGAGAACCGGCCUCCUGCUCGAGUUCAGAGCUCAUCUGAGGAAUUGGAAUUGAGACACCAAAGCCUAGACGCGUUUCCUGGACGACGGCUUCCCGGCAGGGGCAUCCAGCCAGCGGCCAAGAUGUCGUCAGUGGGGAAGGUGACCCAGGUUCCGAAUGGGAAAGCCUACCAGCAGAUCUUCCAGGCUGAGGUGCAGCUGGUCCACUCCCUGGCGGCCACCAGGAAGCGGGCUGCAGAGCGUUCUGUGACCCUGAAGAGUGGCAGGAUACCCAUGAUGAAGAAGGUGGAGACUCCUGAAGGGGAGGUGAUGUCUCCCCGACAGCAGAAGUGGAUGCACAGCCUCCCCAACGACUGGAUCAUGGAAAACCCUGUUCUCCACAGGGAAAAGGAAAGAGCCAAGAGGGAAAAAGCCCGAGAGAGUGAGAACACCAUCGCUGCCCGAGAAGUGCGGGGUCUCAUGGAUACUAUAGUUCCUGAGAAGAUAAGCACCAGCACCUUUCAAAGGCAAGCAGAACACAAGAGGAAGAGCUACGAGAGCGCUCUGGCCAGCUUUCAGGAGGAGAUUGCGCAGGUGGGAAAGGAAAUGGAACCUCUCAUCGUGGACACAGGGGGACUUUUUUUGAAGAAGCUGACUGAGUCUGAUGAAGAAAUGAACCGUCUCUUCCUAAAGGUGGAAAAUGACACCAACCUUGAGGACUACACCAUCCAAGCCCUGCUGGAGCUGUGGGAUAAGGUGGCCGGGCGGUUACUGCUCCGGAAGCAGGAGAUUAAGGAGCUGGAUGAGGCCCUGCACUCGCUGGAGUUCUCCCGAACCGAUAAACUAAAAAGCGUGUUGAAGAAAUAUGCAGAAGUCAUAGAGAAAACUUCCUACCUCAUGCGGCCCGAAGUGUACAGGCUGAUAAAUGAAGAAGCCAUGGUCAUGAACUAUGCCCUGCUGGGCAACCGGAAGGCUCUCGCCCAGCUGUUUGUCAACCUGAUGGAGUCCACCCUGCAGCAGGAGCUGGACAGCCGCCACCGCUGGCAAGGCUUGGUGGACACCUGGAAGGCUCUCAAGAAGGAGGCCCUGCUGCAGAGUUUCAGUGAGUUCAUGGCCAGUGAGAGUAUCCAUACUCCCCCGGCUGUGACGAAGGAGCUAGAGGUCAUGCUGAAGACCCAGAACGUCCUGCAGCAAAGGCGGCUGAAGCAUCUCUGCACCAUCUGUGACCUCCUGCCCCCCAGUUACAGCAAAACUCAGCUGACUGAGUGGCAUUCUUCCCUCAACUCCCUGAACAAGGAGCUAGACACCUACCACGUGGACUGCAUGAUGCGGAUCCGCCUGCUGUAUGAGAAGACAUGGCAGGAGUGCCUGAUGCAUGUGCAGAAUUGUAAGAAGCAGCUGCUGGACUGGAAAGCCUUCACUGAGGAGGAGGCAGAGACCCUGGUGAACCAGUUCUUCUUCCAGAUGGUGGGAGCACUCCAGGGCAAAGUGGAGGAGGACCUGGAGCUCUUGGACAAAUCCUUCGAGACUCUGGCAGAUCAGACAGAGUGGCAGAGUUCACACCUCUUCAAGUAUUUCCAGGAGGUGGUACAACUGUGGGAGGCACACCAGAGCGAGCUGUUGGUGCAGGAGCUGGAGCUGGAGAAGAGGAUGGAGCAGCACCGGCAGAAGCACAGCCUGGAGAGCCAGGUGCAGGAGGCCCACCUCGAUAGGCUCUUGGACCAACUGAGGCAGCAAAGUGACAAAGAAACACUGGCGUUUCACCUGGAAAAGGUCAAAGAUUAUCUGAAGAACAUGAAAUCCAGGUAUGAAUGUUUUCACACCCUCCUGACAAAGGAAGUGAUGGAGUACCCAGCGAUCAUGCUGAAAGAACUCAACUCCUACAGCUCUGCCCUCAGCCAAUACUUCUUUGUGCGUGAAAUCUUUGAACAGAACUUGGCUGGAGAAGUCAUUUUCAAAUUCAGGCAACCAGAAGCACAUGAAAAACCCUCCCAGAAGAGAGUGAAAAAACUGAGGAAGAAGCAAGGGUCUAAAGAGGACAUGACCAGAAGUGAGGAAAGCAUAAGUAGUGGGACAAGUACUGCCAGGUCAGUAGAAGAGGUGGAAGAAGAAAACGAUCAAGAAAUGGAGUCCUUCAUAACUGAAGAGGUGCUGGGGCAGCAGAAAAAAUCUCCACUGCAUGCUAAGAUGGAUGAGUCCAAAGAAGGCUCUAUUCAGGGACUGGAAGAAAUGCAGGUUGAAAGAGAGGGCUCCUUAAACCCAUCCCUGAAUGAGGAGAAUGUGAAGGGUCAAGGAGAAAAGAAGGAGGAGUCAGAGGAGGAAGAUGAGAAGGAGGAAGAGGAGGAGGAGGAGAAGCUGGAGGAAGAGAAGGAGGAGAAGGAGGCACAGGAAGAGCAAGAGAGUUUAUCUGUGGGUGAGGAAGAAGACAAGGAAGAGGGUCUAGAGGAGAUAUACUAUGAGGACAUGGAGUCCUUCACAAUCUCCAGUGGAAACACUUAUUUUGUCUUUGUACCCCUGGAAGAAGAGCAUUGUAGGAAGUCCCAUUCCACCUUCUCAGCCAUGUUCAUCAACGACACUUCCAGUGCCAAGUUCAUAGAACAAGUGACAAUUCCAUCGAGACUAAUUUUAGAAAUUAAGAAACAACUUCGAGCUGGCUUCUUCGAGCACCUUGAGAAGUGGUUUGACCAGUGUUCCCUCAACACCCGGGUCACCGUGGCCACCAAAAUCAAUGAGCUGGAUUCAGAACUGGAGCUGCAUCUGCACCUGCACCAGCCAAGAGCCCAGCAGAUUGAAAAAGACAUCCACAACGUCAGGGCAGCCGAGCUUUUGCUUCAUCAAGAGCAGUUGGACAGCCACUGUGCUGGGGUGACCGAGACGCUGAAGAAGAAGCGGCUGAUGUUCUGCCAGUUCCAAGAAGAGCAAAACGUGAGGAGCAAAAACUUCCGCCUUAAGAUCUAUGACAUGGAGCACAUCUUCUUGAAUGCCACCAGGAGCCAAAAGCUGGUCACUCUCAGCAACACACUGCACCAGGAGUUGCUUAGCUAUGUUGAUGUCACCCAGGUGUCCCUGCGCAGCUUCCGGCAGUACUUGGAGGAGAGUCUGGGCAAACUCCGCUACUCAAAUAUUGAGUUCAUCAAACACUGCAGAUUGUUUUCAGAGGGAGGCAACUUUUCUCCUAAAGAAAUCAAUUCACUGUGUUCCCGACUGGAGAAGGAAGCUGCCCGGAUAGAGUUGGUUGAAAGUGUCAUCAUGCUCAACAUGGAGAAGUUGGAGAAUGAGUACCUGGACCAGGCCAAUGAUGUCAUCAACAAGUUUGAAAGCAAAUUCCAUAACCUGUCUGUGGACCUUAUUUUCAUAGAGAAAAUCCAGCGGUUGCUGACGAAUCUGCAAGUGAAAAUCAAGUGCCAGGUGGCAAAAUCCAAUUCGCAAACAAAUGGAUUAAAUUUCUCUCUGCAACAGCUUCAGAACAAGAUAAAAACUUGUCAAGAGUCCAGGGGAGAGAAAACCACAGUGACCACAGAAGAACUCCUCAGCUUCGUCCAAACUUGGAAGGAAAAACUGAGCCAGAGGAUUCAGUACCUUAACUGCAGCCUGGACAGGGUGUCCAUGACUGAACUGGUCUUUACCAACACCAUCCUGAAGGACCAGGAGGAAGACAGUGACAUCCUGACAUCUUCAGAAGCCCUUGAAGAGGAGGCCAAGCUGGACGUGGUCACCCCUGAGUCCUUCACCCAGCUGAGCCGCGUGGGGAAGCCCCUGAUUGAGGACCCAGCUGUGGAUGUGAUCAGGAAGCUCCUGCAACUUCCCAACACAAAAUGGCCAACCCACCAUUGUGACAAAGAUCCGUCCCAGACAGGUAGAGGCGCAUGGGCCUGUGGGUCUCGGGGCAGCAGUGAGGCAGGGGCUGGUGGUGCUGUGUGCUCACCUCCUGUCCUCUGCUCCUGUCCUGGGCCCUCGUCACCCAAAGGCUUCAAGCGACAUCGGUGCCAGCCAGAAAACUCUGGGAAGAAGGCUGUACCCAGUGCCAGUGCUACCUCUGCAGGCAGCUUCACACCGCACCCCAAGCCCAACAAAAUGGAGAGAAAGUACCGGGUGCUUGGGGACAAGCCUCCCCCUGCUGCCGAGGAUUUUAAGGGGAUCAUCUUGACCCUCCUCUGGGAGAGCAGUGAGAACCUGCUGACAGUCGCAGAGGAGUUCUACCGUAAAGAAAAACGCCCAGUCACCAGGCCUGACUGCAUGUGUGACACCUUUGACCAGUGCGCCGAGAACAUUAGCAAAAAGAUCCUGGAGUAUCAGAGCCAGGCAAAUAAGUACCACAACUCCUGCCUCAUAGAAUUACGGAUCCAGAUCAGGAGAUUUGAGGAGCUGCUGCCCCAAGUGUGUUGGCUGGUGAUGGAGAAUUUCAAGGAACACCACUGGAAAAAGUUUUUCACCUCUGUGAAGGAGAUCCGAGGACAGUUCGAGGAACAGCAGAAGCGGCUGGAGAAAAGAAAGGACAAAAAUGCCCAGAAGCUCCAUCUAAAUCUUGGACACCCCGUACAUUUCCAAGAAAUGGAGUCUCUACACUUAAGUGAAGAGGAAAGGCAGGAAGAGCUGGACAGCAUGAUUAGGAUGAACAAGGAGAAGCUGGAGGAAUGUACCAGAAGGAAUGGCCAGGUUUUCAUAACCAACUUGGCCACCUUCACCGAGAAGUUCCUACUGCAGUUGGAUGAGGUGGUCACCAUUGACGAUGUCCAGGUUGCAAGGAUGGAGCCCCCCAAACAGAAAUUAUCAAUGCUCAUACGAAGGAAACUCGCUGGGCUCUCCCUGAAGGAAGAGAGUGAGAAACCCCUGAUUGAACGUGGAAGCAGGAAGUGGCCAGGGAUCAAACCCACCGAAGUCACCAUCCAAAACAAGAUUCUUCUCCAGCCAACAUCAUCGAUUUCCACCACCAAAACCACCCUGGGCCACCUGGCGGCCGUGGAAGCCCGAGAUGCUGUGUACCUGAAAUAUUUAGCAUCAUUUGAGGAGGAGCUAAAGAGGAUCCAGGAUGACUGUACAUCUCAGAUAAAGGAGGCUCAGCGCUGGAAGGACAGCUGGAAGCAGUCCCUGCACACUAUCCAAGGCCUGUAUGUGUGACCCUCCGCCCCACCAUGAAUAAACACUUUCUUAUACAGACUCCUUCCCUGUCCAUCUACCUGCCUACCUACUUUCCGUCCAUCCCUCCCUCCCUUCAUCCCUCCACCCCUGCUCUGUGCCGGGCACUGUAGCUUUACCAGCGAACAGGACACAGCAUGGUCCCUGCCCACGUGGAGCCCUCUUCCCAUGAGGAAGGCAAGCAUGAAAGGGGAAUUCCACGUGGUUAGCAGGGAGGGUGAGUACCAGGAAUCAGUCACUUCAAAUAGGCACCAGAGCUUCAAAGGACAUCACCUCCAAACAGCAUGCUGGGCAGGGCACGUCAUCUUGAAAAAUGAAAUAAAGGUCAUGGGAAAAUGAUAUUUUAAUUUAACAGAAUAAACAAGUAUGGGUUAUAAUUGCAACUCUGCACUGGUUCCUAGACCCAACAAAUAACUAAUCCAAUGUUGAUUGGUAUUUGUGCCACAAUUUGUCUGAGCAAAUUGCAAUAUUUUGGAAAAAAAAAAAUCUUCCAGGCUCCUUUAGUCCUGUGUUGCCCAGAUCAUUCUCUUGGAGUCCUCCAGCCUGCCAGUCUCUUGUUCGUCAACUCUCUUCUUCAAUUACAUGGCGUGAGCGUACAGCCUUCAUUUGUCGGUAGCUGUGUGUGUCAUCUGGACAGGUUUCCUCAGCCAUAGACCUAGGAGGCCCCAGCUCCCAAAUUUCCAGCCCCUGAAAGCUGUGUGACCCUCCAAGUGCAGUUCCCUCACCUGGGGACACUCACUCUGCUCUCCUGGUUUGCUCCACCCAGUGAGGCCCUGCUUGGUUAGCUUGGUUAGCUUGGUGGCCUUUGUGCACUGAAGCCAGGAGAGUGAGGAGUCCCCUUCCAUCAAGGCAAAAGCAAUCUCCUGUUCUUUUCUGUGCUCCCCCCACCCCCACCCCAAUGUGCUACCUUUCAUUGCUUAUUAUUCCGAAAGGAAUAUAUGCGCAUUGUAGAAAAAAGAAUUUAUGAAACCAGCAAAAGGAUAACUUUAAAAUCCUGAGCCGGGCGCGGUGGCUCACGCCUGUAAUCCUAGCACUUUGGGAGGCCAAGGCGAGCAGAUCAUCUGAGCUCAGGAGUUCGGGGCCAGCUGAGGCAACAUGACGAAACCCCAUAUCUACUAAAAAUACAAAAAGUUAGCCAGGCAUGGUGGCACACACCUGUAAUCCCAGCUACUGGGGAGGCUGAGGCAUGAGAAUCGCUUUAACCUGGGAGGUGGAGGUUGCAGUGAGCCAAGAUCAUGCCACUUCACUCUGGCCUGAGCAACAGAAUGAGACUCUGUCUCAAAUAAACGAAUAAAUAAAUAAUAAAAUCCUGGAAUCUAGAGACAGUCACUGUCCAUAGCAUCUUUCCAUGUAUGUGAGUUAUUUUUAUAAAAUGGAAUCAUAACAUGCAUUAGGUUCCAUAAACUGCUUGGUAAAUGUUAACUGGAUAAACCCUAUGCCAUAUCCUUCAGUAUUCAUUUACAUCAUUGGUUUUCAUACUUUUCUGACUCUGACCCACUGUAUAAACAUGUUCUAAACACACGGUCCUUGCACACAUACACAACUUGAGACCAACAGGUCACAGGACAGCACUUAACCUUACUAGAAAGGCUGCUUUCUAAUAUUUUCUCCCUGCUUUUUAAAUCCUAGCCCAGUCCACUAACUCAGUUCAUGGCCCACAAAGGGGCUUUGAUUGCAGUGUGGGACACUGUCAUUUAAACAGCUGCAGAGUGUUCCCACUGCCUGGGGAACCAGAUCGCCUCUGUCGGACAAGGGCGAGGAUGUCCCAUGCAGGGCUCCUAGAAAGAAGGCAGAGAUGACAUCCUCCCACAUUAGCUCUUUGUACACAUCUGUAAUCAU